ACAGACCCGGAAGCGGAUGGCGUGGACUGAAAGUUGCACGGCGGCGUGUGCGUUUCCUAGUUGUCUGGUGCUGCUAUAUAGGGGACGUGGGGUCCCCACAGACCUGCAGGUUCCGGCCCCUCUUUUCUCAACCCAGAGCAAAUUGAAACGUCCGGGUGAGAGUCCGAUUUCCAAAGACUCAUGUUACGUGAGGAAGCCACCAAGAAGAGCAAAGAAAAGGAGCCAGGGAUGGCUCUUCCUCAGGGACGCUUGACUUUCAGGGAUGUGGCUAUAGAGUUCUCUUUGGAGGAGUGGAAAUGCCUGAACCCUGCACAGAGGGCUUUAUACAGGGCUGUGAUGUUGGAGAACUACAGGAACCUGGAGUUUGUGGAUAUCUCUUCCAAAUGCAUGAUGAAGGAGUUCUCAUCCACAGCGCAAGGCAAUACAGAAGUGAUCCACACAGGGACAUUGCAAAGACAUGAAAGUCAUCACAUUAGAGAUUUUUGCUUCCAGGAAAUUGAGAAAGAUAUUCAUAACUUUGAGUUUCAGUGGCAAGAAGAGGAAAGGAAUGGUCACGAAGCACCCAUGACAGAAAUCAAAGAGUUGACUGGUAGUACAGACCGACAUGAUCAAAGGCAUGCUGGAAACAAGCCUAUUAAAGAUCAGCUUGGAUCCAGCUUUCAUUCGCAUCUGCCUGAACUCCACAUAUUUCAGCCUGAAUGGAAAAUUGGUAAUCAAGUUGAGAAGUCUAUCAUCAAUGCCUCCUUAAUUUUGACAUCCCAAAGAAUUUCUUGUAGUCCCAAAACCCGUAUUUCUAAUAACUAUGGGAAUAAUUCCCUCCAUUCUUCAUUACCCAUACAAAAAUUGGGAAGUACACAUGAGAGAAAAAUCUUUCCAAUGUAAUGAGAGUGGCAAAUCCUUUAAUUAUAGCUAACUCUUAAGGAAAUAUCAGAUAAUCCAUUUAGGAUAGAAACAAUAUAAAUGUGAGGUAUGUGACAAGGUCUUUAAUCAGAAUUGAUUCCUUGUAUGCCAUAAUAGAUGUCACACUGGUAAGAAACCUUACAGUUGUUAUGAGUGUGGCAAGACCUUCAGUCAGACGUCAUCCUUUACAUGCUAUCGUAGACUUCAUACUGGAGGGAAACCUUACAAGUGUAGUGAGCAUAACAAGACCUUUGGUUGAAAUUCAGCCCUUGUAAUUCAUAAGGCAAUUCAUACUGGAGAGAAUCCUUGCAAGUGUAAUGAAUGUGGCAAGGUUUUUAAUCAGAAAGCACACCUUGCACGUCAUCAUAGACUUCAUACUAGAGAGAAGCCUUACAAAUGUGAAGAAUGUGAAAAAGUUUUCAGUCGCAAAUCACAUCUUGAAAGACAAAACUUAAAAGAGGUGGCGUUGCCCUUGUUUUUGAGAAUGCCCUACUGUGUAAGUGGUAGUGUUCUUUCUUUUUUUUUUUUUUUUAAGACGGAGUCUCACCUGAGCGAGCCUCUGCACUGGCCUUAUUUAUUAUUGUUAUUAAUUUUUUGUUUUUGAGACGGAGUUUCACUCUUAUUGCCCAGGCUGGAGUGCAAUGGUGCAAUCUUGGCUCACUGCACCCUCUGUCUGUUGGGCUCAAGCGUUUCUCUUGCCUCAGCCUCCCAAGUAGCUGGGACUACAGGUGCAUGCCACCACGCCUGGUUAAUUUUUGUAUUUAUAGUGGAGAUGGGGUUUCUCCAUAUUGGUCAGGCUGGUCUUGAACCCUUGACCUCAGGUCAUCCACCCGCCUCGGCCUUCCAAAACGCUGGAUUUACAGGCUUGAGCCACGCGUCCGGCCUGAAGUGGUAUUUUUUAGAAAGUAACUAAACCUUUUUUCAGUUUAAUGACCCAGGGAUGUAUUUCUGAAGGACUUGGGAGCGAUCCUUUUAAGGCAAACAAGGGAGAUAGUACCUGUAUCUUAGUAGGAAAUUAAAUAAUUCAAACAUCAAAUGUUUCAAAUUAAAAGCUACCGACCUUUAAAUAAUUCUGAGCCUUGAGAGGAACGUGGUCAUGCAACAAGAGUCCAGUGGCAUGCAGGCACAAGGUUUUUUCUUUUUUGUUUUUUGUUUUUUUUUGAGACAGUCUCGCUCUGUCGCCCAAGCUGAAGUGCAGUGGUGCGAUCUCAGCUCACUGCAAGCUCCGCCUCCUGGGUUCACGUCAUUUUCCUGUCUCAGCCUCCCCAGUAGCUGGGACUCCAGGCACCCACCACCACUCCCGGCUAAUUUUUUGUAUUUUUAGUACAGACAGGGUUUCACUGUGUUAGCCAGGAUGGUCUUGAUCUCCUGACCUUGUGAUCCACCCACCUCAGCCUCCCAAAGUGCUGGGAUUACAGGCAUGAAUGACCGCGCCCAGCCGCAGGCGCAACUUUUUUGAGUUUUCCUGGCCAGGCGCAGUGGCUCAAGCCUGUAAUCCCAGCAUUUUGGGAGGCCGAGGUGGGCGGAUCACUUGAGGUCAGGAGUUAGAAACCAGCCUGGCCAACGUGGUGAAACCCCGUCUCCAGUAAACAUACAAAGCCAUUACAGGGCAUGGUGGGGCACGCCUGUAUUCCCAGCUACUUGGGAGGCUGAGGCAGGAGAACUGCUUGAUCCGGGGAGGUGGAAGUUGCAGUGGGCCAAGAUCAUGCCACUGCACCCCAGCCUGGGCAACAGAGCAAGACUCCGUACC